ACUUCCGGCAGGCGGCGGGGCCCGGAAGCGGCGCGCGGGGCCGGCGAAUCCCGCGGCGCCAGGUGGGAGCGGGGCCGGAGCAUGCGGGGCGGCCGGCGGUCUGCGGCGCGCGGCGCAUUCGUUCCCCCGCGGCGGUGGCGGUGGCGCGCGGCGGCUCUCCAGUGAGCGGCGGAGCCCGGAGCGGCGGGCUGGGCGCCGGGCGGGCGGGGCUCGCGGCUGAGAGGCGGGCGGGCCGGGGGCGCCGGGCGCGGGGCCGCCAUGUGGAGCGGCCGCAGCUCCUUCACCAGCUUGGUGGUGGGCGUGUUCGUGGUCUACGUGGUGCACACCUGCUGGGUCAUGUACGGCAUCGUCUACACCCGCCCGUGCUCCGGCGACGCCAACUGCAUCCAGCCCUACCUGGCGCGGCGGCCCAAGCUGCAGCUGAGCGUGUACACCACGACGAGGUCCCACCUGGGUGCUGAGAACAACAUCGACCUGGUCUUGAAUGUGGAAGACUUUGAUGUGGAGUCCAAAUUUGAAAGGACAGUUAAUGUUUCUGUACCAAAGAAAACGAGAAACAAUGGGACGCUGUAUGCCUACAUCUUCCUCCAUCACGCUGGGGUCCUGCCGUGGCACGACGGGAAGCAGGUGCACCUGGUCAGUCCUCUGACCACCUACAUGGUCCCCAAGCCAGAAGAAAUCAACCUGCUCACCGGGGAGUCUGAUACACAGCAGAUCGAGGCGGAGAAGAAGCCGACGAGUGCCCUGGAUGAGCCAGUGUCCCACUGGCGACCGCGGCUGGCGCUGAACGUGAUGGCGGACAACUUUGUCUUUGACGGGUCCUCCCUGCCUGCCGAUGUGCAUCGGUACAUGAAGAUGAUCCAGCUGGGGAAAACCGUGCAUUACCUGCCCAUCCUGUUCAUCGACCAGCUCAGCAACCGCGUGAAGGACCUGAUGGUCAUAAACCGCUCCACCACCGAGCUGCCCCUCACCGUGUCCUACGACAAGGUCUCACUGGGGCGGCUGCGCUUCUGGAUCCACAUGCAGGACGCCGUGUACUCCCUGCAGCAGUUCGGGUUUUCAGAGAAAGAUGCUGAUGAGGUGAAAGGAAUUUUUGUAGAUACCAACUUAUACUUCCUGGCGCUGACCUUCUUUGUCGCAGCGUUCCAUCUUCUCUUUGAUUUCCUGGCCUUUAAAAAUGACAUCAGUUUCUGGAAGAAGAAGAAGAGCAUGAUCGGCAUGUCCACCAAGGCAGUGCUCUGGCGCUGCUUCAGCACCGUGGUCAUCUUUCUGUUCCUGCUGGACGAGCAGACGAGCCUGCUGGUGCUGGUCCCGGCGGGUGUUGGAGCCGCCAUUGAGCUGUGGAAAGUGAAGAAGGCAUUGAAGAUGACUAUUUUUUGGAGAGGCCUGAUGCCCGAAUUUCAGUUUGGCACUUACAGCGAAUCUGAGAGGAAAACCGAGGAGUACGAUACUCAGGCCAUGAAGUACUUGUCAUACCUGCUGUACCCUCUCUGUGUCGGGGGUGCUGUCUAUUCACUCCUGAAUAUCAAAUAUAAGAGCUGGUACUCCUGGUUAAUCAACAGCUUCGUCAACGGGGUCUAUGCCUUUGGUUUCCUCUUCAUGCUGCCCCAGCUCUUUGUGAACUACAAGUUGAAGUCAGUGGCACAUCUGCCCUGGAAGGCCUUCACCUACAAGGCUUUCAACACCUUCAUUGAUGACGUCUUUGCCUUCAUCAUCACCAUGCCCACGUCUCACCGGCUGGCCUGCUUCCGGGACGACGUGGUGUUUCUGGUCUACCUGUACCAGCGGUGGCUUUAUCCUGUGGAUAAACGCAGAGUGAACGAGUUUGGGGAGUCCUACGAGGAGAAGGCCACGCGGGCGCCCCACACGGACUGAAGGCCGCCCGGGCUGCCGCCAGCCAAGUGCAACUUGAAUUGUCAAUGAGUAUUUUUGGAAGCAUUUGGAG